GCCUGGAGCGCGGCAGCAAGCGUGGGAACGCGGGCGGCGAGACGGCGGCAGGACGGCGGCAGGUAGGCACAGUGGGCGGGUAGGGCGCCCGUGUCCCGCGCGGUCCGGUCCCGCGGGGUCCCCGACGCCAGGCGGGGCGUGGGGGUGGAACUACCUACCGUAAUGUCCCCGGGCGCAGCUCAGUGGCCACCCGUGUCCCUCUCUGCUUUUUGCCUAUUUUCCAGCCACCUAAGUCCAAUCUGAAUGCCCAAGUCGUUGAUUGUCGUUUGCCUGUUUCCAAAGAUUGGUAGAUAGAUGCCUUUUUAAAAAUCUCAUUUUUCUUUAAAUCUGGUUUACAUGGAAAACGUUAGGAGAGCUCAUAUAAUGAACGGCAAUAGCAACCCCCUAUCUUGAAACGCGCUCUAUCAUCCCACUGAAAUUCUACCACGUGGAAUAAUGCUUGGAGGGUCAGAGUUGUGGAACUGCCCAAUAACCAGUCGUUACUGAGGGUUAGUUUGUGAAGGAGGGGACAGACUGCUUCUAAAAUUCUGUUUAAUGACAGUCAAUUAAGAUUUCUGAGUCUGGCUUGAGGGCCUUUGCUUCCAUCACAGCCCAGUCGUCCUUGGCAAGAGAGUCUGUAUAUGGGCCACAGCUCACAAAAGCAUUGUUUGAAAAAAUUUAUUGAAAGAACAUUGUUUGUAAAAUGAGUCCCAAUACAUAGGACAGACUUUCCUAAGGUGAGAUGUGUUACUUACCCAGAGCUGUGAAAGGCUUUACGGAUGGAAACUAGAGACUGAAUUUUCCAGAAUUUUAAGAAGUCUCCCCAACCAAUGGCCCCCCACUUUCUUUUUUUAAACCAAAGGUAAGAACUGGUAGUUAAAAUGACAGUUCAAAGCUUGUCCUUUUGGGUUACGGCAGCUUCCUCUAUGAAAAGAUUUGGGAGUGAUUCAGUCACUUGAGGAAGGUUGGUGCCAGAGAGAGAAAUGGCUUUGGUGCUUUCUGGUCUAGUGAUGCGGGUAUGCUAGGCCAGAGCGAGUGCCCUGGGCCCUCCGAGGCGGGGGAGAGGGUGGGGUCUGCUGCUGCCAGCUCAGGUGUGACCUGUAAUCUGGAUUAGGUGGGCCCAGGGCAACCUCUUAUCACGUCCCUCCUGGAAAGCCUGACUGCUGUAUACAUUUCUAGGGCUGCAGAUAGGGCUUGGCCAAUAGAUUACCUCAAAAUCAAGAAGAGGAAGUUAUAAACAUGUGAUUAGACUUAUUAAUUUUUCCUGGCUGGGCAUUUGGUGGAAUUCGUUUGUUAAUGUUUAAUAAAUCAUUAUGGAUCAUAACUGUAGUAGAAUCUCAGGCUUUUGAUGUUACUUAGAAUCUUGGAGGAGACCACGAAGGACACACAGACGUGGCUGCACAUGUGCAGAGAUCUUGUAACGUAACUAUGGCUUUUCUCUGCACCAUGUGUGAAAUAAGCUGCCGCUGGCGUUGGGGCGCCGGCCUGGGUUCCAACACAGUCCGCUGGCUGCCUCGGUAUUUGCCGUGCCUCUCUGGGCCUCAGUUUUUCCUCUCUUAAAUAAAGAGGGGACUGGAUUAGAUGAUUUCUAAAGUAUUUUCCAGCUUUCAGAUGCUAUGACUUACUCUUCUCUUUUUCCUUUUAAAAUUUCUUUUUCCUGUAAAUCACCAAGAUAGUUGUCCUGAACAGUUUAGAUGUUAUGAAUCCAUUAGGAAUCCUGAUAAGAAAGUGUUGACCCUCUUUCUAGAAAAAUGCGUGUACUAACAAAAUUUUGCUUUUGGUUGCAGGAGGCUCAGGAACUGUGGAUUCUAGUUUAAGAAACUUGUAGCAAGGAAAUCAGGGGAGUUGAAAGUCUCAGAAGCCAACCCCUAUGUUGUGUUCUGGCCACCUCUGUGCAGCUCAUUCCUCAAUCUAGGAGAAAUUUUUCUACCUUGCCCCAGGAAAGAGCUGCUAACUUGUUUUCGGGGAGUGUGGGGGGGUCUUUGGUAUUGGUGUUCCAUUUCUCUUCUCAGGUACCCUCUCCCAAGUCUGUCCCUUCUUUAUGAUAAACACAGUGGCCUGCUUUAGAAUUCUGGGUCUCUUGAGAUACAGCCUCUCAACUUACAGUUGGUCGUAGGAGUUGCCCAGGAAGGAAGUUUGGAUAAUAAUAAUGACAUCUGGCAUGUAAGGUCCAGGCCCUGUCUCAGUUGCUUUCCGUGUAGCAUCUGAAUUCUCUUACAACCAGUACAGGUAGUGUUUUGUUAGCUGCAUCUGGGACUGGGUAGCUGAUGCCCUGAGUUUAAAUGCUGAUCCAGCGUCUCCCAGCUGAGCGGUGGCGGGACUUGAAUGAGAUCGCGGUUCUGUCUCAUUCUCAAACUGCUGCUCUUAUCACUGUGAAGGAACAGCUAUUUAGAUGGGCUGGCCUGAGGGCCUCCUCUUUCCCAGACGGCACGGACGCAGUAUUCUAUCAGGGAAUGUGGGGCCAGCUGGGCAUCUGGUAGCCCAGUUGGUUCUUCGGAUAAUGGGCUGCUCAGUGAAGGAACCUGGUGCUGUAAAAGUGAUUCCCCCUCUCCUUCCAGUCUUGGGCUAAAACUGGAGCUGUUCACUGUGGUUGUAUCUGCCUGAAAGGAAAGGGCAGAUGAAAGCUGGAAGGAGCACAGCCAGCACAGUGGGAGGGGCCUGCAGGGGGCUGCUGGUGGCUGCAGGUUUCCCACGGAGCUUUCAGUUUGCACUCAGGGCUGUGAGGUCAUGGAGGCCAGCAUUGCCUUCUCAUGGCAGGUGUCCCGGAGUCCCUGAAUCUGAUGUGUGACCGGAAUGGUGGUCGGCGGCUUCGACAGUGGCUGAUCGAGCAGAUUGACAGUAGCAUGUAUCCAGGACUGAUUUGGGAGAAUGAGGAGAAGAGCAUGUUCCGGAUCCCUUGGAAACACGCUGGCAAGCAAGAUUAUAAUCAGGAAGUGGAUGCCUCCAUUUUUAAGGCCUGGGCAGUUUUUAAAGGGAAGUUUAAAGAAGGGGACAAAGCUGAACCAGCCACUUGGAAGACGAGGUUACGCUGUGCUUUGAAUAAGAGCCCAGAUUUUGAGGAAGUGACGGACCGGUCCCAACUGGACAUUUCCGAGCCAUACAAAGUUUACCGAAUUGUUCCUGAGGAAGAGCAAAAAUGCAAACUAGGCGUGGCAACUGCUGGCUGCGUGAAUGAAGUUACAGAGAUGGAGUGCGGUCGCUCUGAAAUCGACGAGCUGAUCAAGGAGCCUUCUGUGGACGAUUACAUGGGGAUGAUCAAAAGGAGCCCUUCCCCGCCGGAGGCCUGUCGGAGUCAGCUCCUUCCAGACUGGUGGGCGCAGCAGCCCAGCACAGGCGUGCCGCUGGUGACGGGGUACACCACCUACGACGCGCACCAUUCAGCAUUCUCCCAGAUGGUGAUCAGCUUCUACUAUGGGGGCAAGCUGGUGGGCCAGGCCACCACCACCUGCCCCGAGGGCUGCCGCCUGUCCCUGAGCCAGCCUGGGCUGCCCGGCACCAAGCUGUAUGGGCCCGAGGGCCUGGAGCUGGUGCGCUUCCCGCCGGCCGACGCCAUCCCCAGCGAGCGACAGAGGCAGGUGACGCGGAAGCUGUUCGGGCACCUGGAGCGCGGGGUGCUGCUGCACAGCAGCCGGCAGGGCGUGUUCGUCAAGCGGCUGUGCCAGGGCCGCGUGUUCUGCAGCGGCAACGCCGUGGUGUGCAAAGGCAGGCCCAACAAGCUGGAGCGUGAUGAGGUGGUCCAGGUCUUCGACACCAGCCAGUUCUUCCGAGAGCUGCAGCAGUUCUAUAACAGCCAGGGCCGGCUUCCUGACGGCAGGGUGGUGCUGUGCUUUGGGGAAGAGUUUCCGGAUAUGGCCCCCUUGCGCUCCAAACUCAUUCUCGUGCAGAUUGAGCAGCUGUAUGUCCGGCAACUGGCAGAAGAGGCUGGGAAGAGCUGUGGAGCCGGCUCUGUGAUGCAGGCCCCCGAGGAGCCGCCGCCAGACCAGGUCUUCCGGAUGUUUCCAGAUAUUUGUGCCUCACACCAGAGAUCAUUUUUCAGAGAAAACCAACAGAUCACCGUCUAAGUGCGUCGCUUGGGCGCCCCACCCCGUCUGCGUCCUGCAUCCAUCUCCCUGUUACAGUGGCCCGCAUCAUGAUUAAAGAAUGUGGAUCCCUCUGUCUGGGGUGGGAUGCCUUACUUUGCACUUAAUUUAAUAAGGGCAUUCUCGGAGGAGUAGACGUUUAAUACGAAGUGGCGGCAUAGCCCUGCCGAGAUGUCGGUGAUGGCCUGGAUGCUGUAACCACAACCUGUGGCUAAAAAUUUUAUUUUCUAUCCUUUACCCGUCAUUAUCAUUAGUUGCUAUGAUUCUUUCUGCAUUUUCGGUUAACUAUCAUUUCCAAAGACUUGUCAUUCAGUAAUAUUAGCAGAUAGCUGCUUCGAUAAAGGAAUUUGGAGUUUAAAAAUCAACUUGUGAAAACAAGGUUGUUUUUGUCUUUAUCGUUUGUUAGAGUUAUAGAUUUAUGAUUUCAUAGGCUUGAUUCUAUGUGAAAUAUCUUUUUACUUUUAUGCAUUUUAAUAAGAUUUAAAAAUAUUUAGAUUAAAGCCCCCUUUAAUGAGUACAAGAAAAACUCUUGGCUUGUUAGAAGAAAGUAUAUUCUUUCUAGAAUUUGGUGCAGGAAUAUGUGUUCAUAUCCAGGCAAACGGGUGUGUUUUUAUCUUCAGACAAUGAAACCUUCUCCUCUGGGGCUUUGUUGCCAGGAAGAUUAGAACUAAAUUUAUUUUUUUCAUUUCUGUCAUGAAAUCAUUCCAGAUACCUCUUUUCUUCUUUCCAAAUGGUUUUCACAUGUGUUUGAAAUAUUUGUACUUCGAAUUGUCGGAUUUUCCAUGUCCUCCUUUCUCCUUUGUGCCCAGCCUGAGUCAGCACCAAUCCCGCAUUCAGAACCUCCCAGUGAAAGGGCAGCCUUCAUUUUGAGAAGGUGGAAGGUGUUAGGGUUUGGGAGACAGCUCAUCCAAUCUCCCAAGUCUCAUGGUGGAUUUGUGACUGUGAGAGUUUCCGGUUUAAAAUCUGAAAAGCCAGAUAUGCCUGUUUCCUUUUCCCAGCACCAUGCCUGUGGAGGGGACAGUCAGACCCAGAGGUCCUUUACGUGUGGAUGGAGUUCACAGGCGAAUAGAGGAGAGGACCAGGGGACGUGGCUUGUCCCUUUUGUCCAACAAAGCAUUAUAUUUUUAAGAAUGGCAGACCUGUUUGCUGAAGUGUUCAUAAGAUAACAAUAGGCUUGAAUCUCCAAUUCAAAUGAAUGUCAAAGCACAUAUCUUUAAUAUGCUGAAUGAAUAUUUAUUUUUGUAUCCAUUAAAACAGUAUAUUGAUCUCUUUUAUUCUUUAUUAAAAUAAAAUGCUCUUUUUUAAAGCU